GGGAGAAGAGGGCGGCGGGACCUUUCCUGGCGCCGCUCGCAGUUUACAUGUGGAUUUAUUCAUUCUGGAGAUACAAUGGCAAGGAAACAGCUGUGGAUCAUCAGGGAAGGAAGACCUCUCUGAGGAGUUGAUGUUUUACCUGGAGACCUAAAUGAUGAGGAUUUAAAAGCUUUUCGGACAACAGCAAUUACAAAUGCAAAGACCUUGAGAGUCUUGCUGUGUGGCCCAGGCUGGAGUGCCCGGCUGGUCUCAAAUUCCUGACCUCAAGUGAUCUCCCUCCCAAAGUGUUGCGAUUGCAGGUGUGAGCCACUGCACCUGGCUGCUGAGAAAUCUUUGCCUACAGUGAGGGAAACUACUAAAGUUCCUGGGGAAGCAAAGUAGAAUUUCAUAAGAACAAAAUGGAUGGAGAGGAGAAAACCUAUGGUGGCUGUGAAGGACCUGAUGCCAUGUAUGUCAAAUUGAUAUCAUCUGAUGGCCAUGAAUUUAUUGUAAAAAGAGAACAUGCAUUAACAUCAGGCACGAUAAAAGCCAUGUUGAGUGGCCCAGGUCAGUUUGCUGAGAACGAAACCAAUGAGGUCAAUUUUAGAGAGAUACCUUCACAUGUGCUAUCGAAAGUAUGCAUGUAUUUUACGUACAAGGUUCGCUACACUAACAGCUCCACCGAGAUUCCUGAAUUCCCAAUUGCACCUGAAAUUGCACUGGAACUGCUGAUGGCUGCGAACUUCUUAGAUUGUUAAAUAAAAUAAAUUAUAAUAAACUGUUAACUCUUUUCAGUAUUUAAUACCUGUAGUUCAGUUAGUAACUUUUUCAUAUAUAGCAUGUUGCCUGUAUGCAGUUGAACUAUAUAAAGUUCAUUGCAAAGCAGAUUAUCUUGUUUUUUUGCAUAGCAAUCAAAGUUGAAAUUUGUUUGCUACAUCAACAAAUUAAGGACAUUUUCACAAACUGAGAAAUAAACAAAUAUGCCAAUUCGUAGGUGGUUUUGCCUUAUCCUUUGAAUGUGACUUAAAAUCAGCAAUGAUGAUAUAGUAAAUACUGAAAUUUAGGUGUAAAUCAAUACGUUCUACAGGGAAAUAAUGAGGCUAAGUAUUUUUAUGUUUUUAGUGGUUUUUUAGAAACCUAAUCUUAUAGCCGCCAUUAGCAUUACUAGAGUUAUGCAAAUAAUUGCAUUAUAAACAUGUUUAUAACUUAGCCAAAACAUUGAUUUUUAUAACUCUCCAAGUAUGAGUUGAAAUUUCUUAUGUCUUUUGAUAAACUGCAGUAUUCUUUAAGUGUACUUUGUCCUUUUGUUUAUUGCUACAAUUUAAGAACUUUAUUUAAAAACAAUUUUGGAAGGUUACUAGGUACAGCUUUUGCAGAAGAAACUGAACUGUAGCCAGAUGGUCAGCAAGUAAACUACAUGACUUAGAGUUCUUGUGCAUUAUACAUUUUGGGUAAUUCAAAGUACUGUAUUUGCAUUGACUAUAAAGCGUCGUUUGCAAUAUUUAUUCUUCCUUCAUAGUCCCUUGUUGUGAUUAUACUUCCAGUUGUUUAAAUGUAUUUUAAAAGACUCACUAUUAACUUUAUUCAGAUCUUAAAAGCUACACCUUUUUGAACUAUUCCAGUCUUUCUCCAUCCAAUUAGAAUGUUAUGGAAUAACAUGUGAAGAGAUACAGUGAAAAUCAUAUUAUAAUGCAUUGAAGAUAUCCUACAUGAAUUAUCUUCUAUUAAAAUAUGUCCCAAUAAAUAUACCCAUAAUCAGUGGGUCUUCUACUGAAAUCAAGCUCAUUCAGCUUUUCUAUUAAGCAGCCAAAAAAUUUUUUGAAAAAAUAUGACAGCAUCAUUCCUUAUGCAUGGGGAAAGAAGCACUGGAGAUGGGUUUAGUAUUGUCUUUAUCUCAGAGGUGGAACAAAGUUGUCAUUAUAGGGUCUAUAAACUUAAGUCUCCAGCUUAUUUGAGACUGGCUUAAUAUGGCUGAGCCCGGUGGCUCAUGCCUGUAAUCCCAGCACUUUCAGAGGACGAGGCGGGUAGAUCACUUGAGGCCAGGAGUUUGAGACCAGCCUGGCCACCAUGGCAAAACCCCAUCUCUACCAAAAAUGCAAAAAUUAGCUAGGCCAUGGUGGCACACGCCUGUAAUCCCAGCUACUUGUGAGGCUGAGGCAUGAGAAUCGCUUGAACCUGGGAGGUGGAGGUGGCAGUGAGCCGAGAUCGCACCACUGCACUCCAGCCUGGGUGACAGAGCGAGACUGUCUCAAAAAAAAAAAAAAAAAAA